AGUGGCUCACCCUCAGUCAACAGGCCAGACUCAAGGGGUUCCUGGCAAGUCAUUUCUCCCUCAGGCCUUCGGUUUCCUCACCUACAAGAUGAGAGGGCUGGACCAGAUGGCAAUUCAGGGGGGUCCGUAUCUCCUGCUGGGUGAGGUCCUUGGACACAGCGCACUUGGUGCGCAGCCCGCGCAGGCUGCCAACGGAGAUGCCGAUGAGCUUCUGGAGCUGCCCGCACUGCUGCAGCGCCCGGCUGGCCGCGGCCCCUGUGCCUCCCUACGCGAUAGCCGCGUCACCCCCGCCACUGCCCUCCUUCUUCUCUCCCAUUGCAGCCGAGCGCAGCGCCGCUCUAUGCGGGCUGCAGCAGCCCAGGAGCGGAGCCCUGGGCGCCGGCGUCUAGGCAAGGAACCCCUGAUUCGGGAGAGCUGGACCAGGAGCGCCCCUUGGCGCUGCCUUAGUCAGGACGCCGGUAGAGCUGGCAGCCAAGUCUGCGGAUCCAGCCCUCAGACCCGCGGCGGUGGGGGCAAAAAACUGCAGCGGUGGAAAGCCGCAGCGGCGGGGGUAAAAAGCAACGGGGGCGGGGGCAAAAACCCGCGGCGGCGGGGGCAAAAAGCGGCGGGGCCGCGGCGGCAAAAAGCCGCAAAAAGCCGGGGCGGCGGGGGCAAGAAGCCGCGGCGGGAAAAACCUGCGGCGGCGGGGGCGAAAAGCCGUAAAAAGCCACGGCGCCGGGGGCCAAAAGUCAUAAAAAGCCGCGGCGGCGGUGGCAAAAAGCCGCGGCGGAAAAAGUCGCGGUGGCGGGGGCAAAAAGCUGCAGCGGCAGGGGGAAAAAAGCCGCAAAAAGCCGCGGCGGUGGGGGGAGAAAGACGCAAAAAGCUGCGGCGGCAAAAAGCCGCGGCUGCGAGGGCAAAGAUCCCCAAAAAGCCGCGGCAGCAGGGGCUAAAUUCCGCGAGGCCGGGGGCAGAAAGCCGUGGUGGCCGGGGCAGAAAGCAACGGAGGCGGGGGCAAAAAGUCGAGGCGGCGGAGGCAUAA